AUUGCUGGGCAACUAGGUCCCGCCGGAGCGUUCCAGCUCAAAGAUUACCUGCUGCAGUCAGGCAGAAAUGUAAAGUCUUUCCUGUUUGAUUGGGAACUGACCCAGGUGCCAGGCUUGGGGGGACACCGGACAACCAAAGGCAAUAUGUGGACUCGGCAAGCCACUGGUCCCUAAACCUGAAUAAGUUUCCGGGCAGAGCUGCAUUUAUUGACGGUUAUGAAAGCUGAUUUAGAAGCAGCAACGCAGCCUCUUGCCUGGAAUUGGGAUGAUGCGGCUGAAACCACCUUCCUGGCAGCCAAACAGGCUAUUCAGCAGGCACAAGCCCUAUGGGUAGCUGAUCGGGGCACCCAUUUAAACUUGAUGUGCAUGUGACCAGAUAGUUUUGACUGGGGCUUAUGGCAUCACACAGAGCUCUUUAGAAUGCCAGUAGACUUUUGGUCCCAACUUUGGAAGGGAGCUGAGCUCCAGUAUUCCUCGACAGAGAAGCAGUUACUAACUGCAUAUGCUGCCCUUUAGACUCGUGACAGCCUGGCAGGAUGGGCUACAGUCGUCGCGCGCAUGACUUACCCAAUAGCAGGCCCCGAGUGUUCUUUCAACUACCUGCCACCCAUCCAACAACUCCCCUCGGACCUCAGUAUGGGCUGGAACCUGACACUUGGCAUGACAGUGCAGACCCCAGGCAUCCAAACCAUGACAGUUCCAUCAGCUCUCCAAAUGAGACUUUGGGAUUCCAGAAGACAGAGGUUUGAGUGUAAAACACAAAAUAACAAAACCACAACAAAAACAACUCUGUAUUCUCGUCCCCACCAUUACCAUCUCUCCUUUGUGAUGUCAAAGAGACCAGAGGAAGUGGACAGACUCGGGGAAGAAUAGCCAGAGUAAGCCUUCCAAAUUAACCCCAGGAAUGGCUUCAACAGAGGAACAGUACGAUCUUAAGAUUGUGAAAGUGGAGGAAGACCCUAUCUGGGACCAAGAAACCCACCUUCGAGGGAACAACUUUUCUGGCCAAGAAGCCUCCCGACAACUUUUUAGGCAGUUUUGUUACCAAGAGACUCCUGGUCCCCGAGAAGCUCUGAGCCGGCUCCGAGAACUCUGUCAUCAGUGGCUAAGGCCAGAAAUCCACACCAAAGAGCAAAUCUUGGAGCUGCUGGUGCUGGAGCAAUUCCUGACUAUCCUGCCUGAGGAGCUCCAGGCCUGGGUGCGGGAGCACCAUCCGGAGAGUGGGGAGGAGGCUGUGGCUGUAGUUGAAGAUCUGGAACAAGAGCUUAGUGAGCCAGGGAACCAGGCUCCAGACCAUGAACAUGGACAUUCUGAAGUGCUCUUGGAGGAUGUGGAACAUCUGAAGGUCAAGCAGGAACCAACAGACAUACAGCUUCAGCCUAUGGUGACACAGCUCAGAUAUGAAUCUUUUUGCCUCCACCAAUUUCAAGAACAAGAUGGUGAAAGUAUACCUGAGAACCAGGAGUUGGCAUCAAAGCAAGAAAUCUUAAAAGAAAUGGAACAUUUGGGGGAUAGCAAACUCCAAAGAGAUGUAUCUUUGGAUUCUAAGUACAGAGAAACUUGUAAACGAGACAGCAAGGCAGAAAAGCAGCAGGCACAUUCCACUGGAGAGAGACGCCACAGGUGCAAUGAAUGUGGGAAAAGCUUCACUAAGAGUUCAGUACUCAUUGAGCACCAGAGAAUCCACACUGGGGAGAAGCCAUAUGAAUGUGAAGAAUGUGGGAAGGCCUUCAGCCGGAGGUCAAGCCUGAAUGAACAUCGGCGGAGCCACACUGGAGAGAAACCCUAUCAAUGUAAGGAGUGUGGGAAAGCCUUCAGUGCCAGCAAUGGCCUCACUCGACACAGAAGAAUCCACACAGGGGAAAAACCAUAUGAAUGCAAAGUGUGUGGGAAGGCUUUCCUCCUCAGCUCAUGCCUUGUUCAGCAUCAGAGGAUACACACUGGAGAGAAGCGCUAUCAGUGUCGUGAGUGUGGCAAAGCCUUCAUUCAGAAUGCAGGGCUUUUCCAGCAUCUCCGAGUCCACACUGGUGAGAAACCCUAUCAGUGCAGUCAGUGCAGUAAACUCUUUAGUAAGCGGACACUUCUUAAGAAACAUCAGAAAAUCCACACUGGAGAGAGACCAUAAGGGUGAUGAGUUUGGGAAAGCCUUCAGUCAUCAUUGCAACCUUAUUAGGCAUUUUAGAAUCCAUACUGUUCCAGCAGAACUGGACUAAUUCUGUGGACCCUCAGACCCCUAAAUGGGGCCGUCUUGGAAAGUAAGAUUUUCAAGUGGCUUAUUCUGUUCUUAUAAAAUUUAUUUUGUAUUGCAUUGAACCACUUGUCUACAAACCAGGUGUUGGUGUCUCCUGUGUGGAUGACUGUGAUUGUAGGGGGUUGCUGGGUGGCCUUCUUAUUCCCUAGCCUUUGGUCCAUUUCUUAUGAUUUCCUUUAAAGGCACCAAAUCUUAUCUGGAAAUAAAUUGUUAUGGAGGGGCUGUUUUUGAGCAAUACUGCAUAUUGAACAAUUCUAAAAGACCAGUAUCUAUGUAUACUUUUAAAAAAAAGAUUUGCUAAGAUCAAAGGAUAUUCAGAGGUGCAUCUUUUUCUGUAAGAGUGACAUUUUAAACAAAUGUAAGGUUUUGGGGAAUAAGAAUCGUCCACAUUCCCACAGGAAAUCAUUGCUAUGGUCUCCCCUAGGAAUGUGAUAGAUAGCUUCUAUAAUUAUGCAGCAUUAUCCAUAGUAUGAAACCUGUAGUUUUAAUGGUUUAGAAAUCUAUGUCUCAUUUCAUAUCUAACUCAUGUUUUUGAUACGAAUCAAUAUAUAUGUUGAUAUCAUGAGUUAAUAUGAGUUUGACAUGAAUCAUCAACAUAGUAUAUACAUAUCAACAUAACUAUGUUGAUGAUUCAUAUCAAAUUCUCAAUGCAGGUCAUUACUGUAAGUUUUCCAUUUUUGUUACAAAUAAUAAGUAAGAUGAUACUUUAAAAUCUCUGUUCUUCACAAGGUACCUCUUUAAUUCAUAGCCUUUUAUGUCAGCAUUAUUCUUCUUUUGGGGGUUGGUCAGCAACUUUGAGUGCCAUUGCAAGCAGCAUCAUUUAAGUAGUUUUAUAAAGAAAAGAAGUCUGAUAUCUUGGGCAGCUUGCUGCUUACUGGGGAGACCAGCAUGCUUAGACACUUAUUGCCAGGGUUAAACAUAUGCUCUGGCACCAAGUUCAAAUCUUUCCUCCCCAUUUGUGAGCUGUGGGACUUUAGGCAAGUUAUCUAAAUGCUGCUAUGCUAUAGUCUCCCCACCUGUAAAACAGAGGAUGAUACCAAUACCUUCCUCAUAGGGUACAUAAGAUUAAAUAAAUACAAACUUGUACUUAAAAUGUAGCUCUCAAUAAAUAUGCAUUAUGAUUUACAUACGAAAUAAUAGCAUUUAACAAAUGUAGGUAGAAUUUUAAGUAUCAUGUUAAAAUUAGGAUACGAAAUGCCUCUGCUGACAUUCUUGUUACUCUUUUCUCCACAGUCAAAACCUGAAUCAGAAUAUUUCAAAAGAGAGGAAAUAAAAGUUCAGCUUAAAACUGUUCUGCCCUAAA